AUGGCUGCCGUACGCCGGGCCCGCAGUUAUUGCCGCUGCCUGGUGCGCUUCUCCGACCGAGAACUCUGCUAA